GCAGCCGGGGUUUGGUACCGAGCGGAGAGGAGAUGCACACGGCACUCGAGUGUGAGGUAACUAUAAAACCCCGAUUUGUUUACAUUCCCUCCCCCAGAACCGGCCCCGUGCGCGGCGGAGACUGCGAGUCCCGGGACGGCGUGGGGGUAGAAAGGGAGAACAGAACCGGGGAGUCGGGGCUGGUUCCCUCGGGGAUGCGGGCGCUGGGGUUCCCGCAGCUGCUGCAGUCGGCGGCGGCCAGCCGAAGCAGAGCGCGUGGUGGGCAGAGUGUUGGGCGCCGCGGCUCCUCGUGUGCGGUCUGGGCUGCUGCGGGCCGCGGGAUCGGGAGCCGGCGGCAUCCACUUCGCGUGCGGAGCCUCGCGCCCCCCUCACCUUCCUGUGGAGGAAAAAUAGAAAUGAAGGUACAUAUGCACACAAAAUUUUGCCUCAUUUGUUUGCUGACAUUUAUUUUUCAUCAUUGCAACCAUUGCCAUGAAGAACAUGACCAUGGCCCUGAAGCGCUUCACAGACAGCAUCGUGGAAUGACAGAAUUGGAGCCAAGCAAAUUUUCAAAGCAAGCUGCUGAAAAUGAAAAAAAAUACUAUAUUGAAAAACUUUUUGAGCGUUAUGGUGAAAAUGGAAGAUUAUCCUUUUUUGGUUUGGAGAAACUUUUAACAAACUUGGGCCUUGGAGAGAGAAAAGUAGUUGAGAUUAAUCAUGAGGAUCUUGGCCACGAUCAUGUUUCUCAUUUAGAUAUUUUGGCAGUUCAAGAGGGAAAGCAUUUUCACUCACAUAACCACCAGCAUUCCCAUAAUCAUUUAAAUUCAGAAAAUCAAACUGUGACCAGUGUAUCCACAAAAAGAAACCAUAAAUGUGAUCCAGAGAAAGAGACAGUUGAAGUGUCUGUAAAAUCUGAUGAUAAACAUAUGCAUGACCAUAAUCACCGCCUACGUCAUCACCAUCGUUUGCAUCAUCAUCUUGAUCAUAACAACACUCACCAUUUUCAUAAUGAUUCCAUUACUCCCAGUGAGCGUGGGGAGCCUAGCAAUGAACCUUCAACAGAGACCAAUAAAACCCAGGAACAAUCUGAUGUUAAACUACCGAAAGGAAAGAGGAAGAAAAAAGGGAGGAAAAGUAAUGAAAAUUCUGAGGUUAUUACACCAGGUUUUCCCCCUAACCAUGAUCAGGGUGAACAGUAUGAGCAUAAUCGGGUCCACAAACCUGAUCGUGUACAUAACCCAGGUCAUUCUCAUGUACAUCUUCCAGAACGUAAUGGUCAUGAUCCUGGUCGUGGACACCAAGAUCUUGAUCCUGAUAAUGAAGGUGAACUUCGACAUACUAGAAAGAGAGAAGCACCACAUGUUAAAAAUAAUGCAAUAAUUUCUUUGAGAAAAGAUCUAAAUGAAGAUGACCAUCAUCAUGAAUGUUUGAACGUCACUCAGUUAUUAAAAUACUAUGGUCAUGGUGCCAACUCUCCCAUCUCAACUGAUUUAUUUACAUACCUUUGCCCUGCAUUGUUAUAUCAAAUCGACAGCAGACUUUGUAUUGAGCAUUUUGACAAACUUUUAGUUGAAGAUAUAAAUAAGGAUAAAAACCUGGUUCCUGAAGAUGAGGCAAAUAUAGGGGCAUCAGGCUCUUUUUUCAUCGUACCCACUUGGCUCCACCUUGGUGUUCACAGGUACCUCCCACUUAAUAUUUCAAAACUUAUACUCCACACAAAAUUUGUACCCCUUAAUGGAUCCCAAAUAUCAUUAAUUUCAUUCUUUUGAUAAAAUCUAGAACUCUUUGACUUUCUUUUUCUCUUUUUUUUCUUUUCCUUUUUUUCCCAUUCUAUAAUCAGGUAUGAAGUCCAGUUAAAGCUAUCUCUUCAGUAUCUUCUAACUUCAUCCACUCUGUCAUAACAAUUCUGGAUUUUCUUGGUUAUUGGAUUGUUGAAAUAACUUCAUAACCUUCCCUGCCUGUGUUCUUGUCCCCUUGCAAGACAUUCUUAGCACUUAAACUAGAUUUACCUUUCUAAAAUGCAAAGAGAUUCUGACACAGAAUUUUUUCUUUAUAGUGAUAGCUAACAUUUUGUUAAUACAUACUUUUUAAAUCUUAUUUACUUAAACACAUAUCGCAGACACUGUUCUAAGCUGAAUUCAUUUACUCCUCACAACACUUUUAUGAGAUAGGUAAUGUUACUCUUCCCAGUAACUUUUCUGAUAUCUCAGAGCUAAUAAGUGGUAGUACUGGGAUUUAGUCCUGUAACCAUUUUGCUAUCUUAUGUGUUGUUUUAAAUGCAUUUUUUUUUCACUAAAUUUUGGCAGUAAUCCUAUGAGGGAGAUAUUAUGAUCCUUGUUUUUAAAAACAAGAUAAGGAAACUGACAGAGCCCACAAACCCUAAGGUUUGUCUGAUGAAACCUCUGAGUAUCUAAUCCCUAUGACAUUGUCUUCCAAAUUAAGUUAGUUCUGGUAUCACCUUUGUGAUUUUUCCCAUAUAUCUUUACACUAUUUAAUACUUUGUAUUUUAUCACUAAUAUAUAUUUUUUAUAUCUCUGGAACAUGGAUUUGAUGUGAUGUGCUAGUUAUAUUUUUUUCUCAUACAUUUUAGGAAACUGCAUCAUGCUAUAUUGUUCAGAGCCCUUUACUUGGCCCACAAGGCUUUCCGUAAUAUGAUCCUCCCUGCCUGCCUUGACAUUCUUAACGCUCAUCAUUCAUUUCUCUCCUCUUUUCUCAGUUCUAACCAUAAUAAACUACUGAUAAUAGAUUGUGCCAUUUUUCUCCCAUCCCUUUCUCCCUCUUCACUUUCUAAACCCCCAUGCCUGACUGACGACUACGAUUCUUCAAAGAUUCAGAUCAAGUAUUGGCCCUUCUGGGUAAACUUAGUGACCAUCCUAGGCUAAAUUAUGUUCCCUUCCUUGACAUCUCUAGAUGUCUCCCUCAUAGUAUAGAUCUUGGGGGAUCUUAAUAAUUGAAUUAAUCUGUUUUUGUUGGACUUUAGUUGCUUUAAUACAGUGACUAAACCAUUUAAGCUCUUAUGUUGAUUGAAUGAAUACAAUUGCUUAAUAUUAGUCUAUAAGCGUUCAGUUAUAAUCCAGGAAAGAUACUUGUUGAAAUGUGUCUUUGAAGAUCAUUAUGUGAAUGUAUCAGUCAGCCUGGUAUACUUCGAUAAUGAAUGUUCUCAAAAUUAGUUGGAUUUUCAUGAACUUUUUUACCAUGAAGUAAUGAAAAACUAUGACGGAAUUACUGUGAACACAGUUCUGGAUGAAAUGCCAAAGACAGAGUGGCUUUAGAGGAUAGUAAUUAAAAUGAGCAAAAUGAUGUAUAUGAAUAUGGACUUAAAACUGAAUUCUGGCAUAAUAAAGGAUUGAGAGGACAGAAUUUUUAAACAUUUCAUAGCAUAGGAAUAAGGUAGACAUCCCAUUCCAAUGUAUAAGAAUUUUAUUUGAGAUAGAGAUACAAGUAAAAGGAAAUAUUAUUACAUAAAAAGUAAAGUCUUCUAGGCACCUACAUUUCUAUUUCUGGUUAAUAUCUUUGCAAUAGGAAAAUAAAUUUAGACUAGAUAAAUUAAUUAUAAUAACCUAUGCUCUCUACUAAAAUACAAAAAAUUAGCUGGAUAUGGUGGUGCGGCCUGUAGUCCCAGCUACUCGGGAGGCUGAGGCAGGAGAAUUGCUUGAACCUGAGAGGCAGAGGUUGCAGUGAGCUGAGAUCACGCCACUGCACUCCAGCCUGGCAACAGAGUGAGACUCCGUCUCAAAACAAAACAAAACAAAAACCUAUGUUUAUUGGGACUUUACCAUGUGCUGUACUAAACAUUUUUACAAGGAUAUUUCUUUUAAUUUAUUAAACCCACUAUACAGGCACUUCUGUUUACUUUCAUUUGGUGAGGAAAAGGAGGCUUAGAGAAUAAGUCAGGUAACUUGCCCAAGGUCACACAAACUGCUGCCAGGUAGCAGAGCCAUGCUAUGAACUAUAGUAUUCUCCUUCUACAACAUAUAAUCAUAACCACUGUGCUGUAAUUCUUAUACUUCCUGUUCUACUGUUUCCUCCUGAAAAGGUUUUGGAGAGUGCUUUGCUAGAAUAUAAGUGGCAGAGAAAUGAGGCCAGUUUUAUAGAAUUAUUUUUAGUAGUAUUUUGACAGAUUUGCAAGUAUUGUUUUAAGUAUAGAUAAGUUGGUGGUUUAAAACAAAAUCCAAGAAUGGUCUUCUUGGUAAACAAGUGGGGCUCUCUGGUAAGAUGAGUAAAAGGAGAGAAAGUGGGGCUUUGAACUGGAUUUGAAUUCUGAUCUUCGAAUAGAUAAAUUUGUCCUCUUUCUUGACUUCAUGCUUAUUGAUCUUGGUGGAUGAAUAAGCGCCCUGAGAGGCCUAGUCCCUCUCAGGUGCCUGUAAAUUCUCACUGUGGCAGGAGAAAGGGGAAGCUAGGUCUGAGAUUAAACUUAAUUAAAAAUAAAAUAGAUUUAUUUGUUCCUUACAGAGAAAAAUGGAGACUGACAAGAUUGAUCUAAAGUUAAAACUAAUAGCUUUUUUUUCUUAUUUUGAAGGCUUCUGAAAAGAUUCUUAUUCUUUGUUGUUAUGUUACCUGUGGAUUAUGACUUUUAAUGAGAGUUGUCUGUAUUGUAAUAUUGCCAUAAUCAAUAUAUUGUAAUGAAGCUGUUGACAGAUGCUUGACUAUAGCAAUACUGAAAGUUACAGCUUAUUCAAUCUGAAAAGCCUUAGAGGAAAUUGUACUUGCUUUGAAAACAAAUAUGUUACUAAUAGUGAAUAUUGAUUAGUUGUUUGCAGGUGGUUAUUAGCAUUGUCAGAAAUGCAGCUUGAAUUAAUUAUGUGCUGAUAGAUGCUAAUAAUUGUUAGAGAUAAUGCCCUGCUAGUAAUUAGUUUUAAUGACUACUGCACCAUUAAGAAAGGUUAACUUGUUCUAUAUAAAUCUCCCAUAGUGGCACAGCUACUACCUCAUUAACUUUGUUCAAAGACUGCUGUAAACCUAAUAUGCUAUAUACUGUGUAUGGUAGAAAUCGUUUGUUUCACAAGAUUGGCUCAUUUAGUCCUAGAGUUGACCCUAGCUUAAUUACCAAGGGGGGAUGUGAAUAGGCUGCUAAGCAUUUUGUGUCAAUUAAAAUGCUGAAGCAGUGUAGAAAACUGCCAUCUUGCACAUGCUUUGAACCAAGUUAAUUAGAAAGUUUCCACAGAUGAGCGCUUCUUUUUAAAAGAAUGCAUUUUCUCUCUAGAUAAUGAGAAAGGGAGUCAGUGAAUAACUAAGCUUGAAGACCUUUAGCAUUUUAAGCAACCCAAUUUGCAGAAUAAGUGAAGCUUGUUUCAGACAUUUGGCGCUUUUUUAUUGCAUAUGGUAUCUUGGGUACAUAUAAAGAAAACAUUUAUUAGUGGUAUUUAAUAGUUUGUAUAUUGUUUUAUAUAAGGUUUUUAAAAGAUACCUUUUGUUUAGUUUUUGCUUUAUACCAAAUGAAUUGUGAUUAAAAAGCACAACAAUUUGGUUAGAAAUCAAAACAAUUUUAUUACCACCAUUGGUUUUUUUUCCUACGUGUAGGAAAUUAGGAUAGAGUUUAUGUAAGCUUAAAUUUAAAUGUUAUAAAUUCUACAAAUAAAGUAUUUAAAUAACAUGGGAAAGUAUUUUAGUACAGUAAGUUCAAAACAACUUCCCAUUUCUGCUCAUAGGUCAAAAGGAUUAUUCCUUGGAAGAUUCCAAGUUGUUAGAAGAAUGAACUAUCAUUUGAAUUUGUAGUGCUUUUAGAAAACUGAAGUUUUUUUAAAAUUAAUAAUUCAGGAUAAGAAGACAUGUUCGUAAUGUUGUAUACUUAGGAGAAUAGUAGUAGGACUGUUUUCCUGAUGAAAUAGUUGUCCAGAAAUAGUUGCAAUCUACAGAAAAUAUCUGGAAAUUUUCUGAUUUAUCUGAAAAGGGAAAUCUAGCUUUUUACUCCUUAUUUGGGACUGGCAGGAGUAAGUGACAAUGUGUGUUACAUGCAAAAUAAAUAAUUAACCUUACUACUUAUGUAUAUUUUUAGUUGGCAUUGAAAUAAAUAUAUUCCGAUAAUUUUAUGUAGUUAUAAGUUUGUUUUGUCAAGGUAGAGAUACUCUUUUGCCUGUCUGCCUCUAUCCUAAUUAGCUCAAAUUUAGAAGGACUGCCAUUUGGAUUAAUAAAGUUAGUAAUCCUUCCUACUUUCAUGUUUAAUUGUACUUUAUAUUUUUAUAGAUUUUCUUUUCUGUGACUCCACCUCUAUGAGGUAAACACAGGAGUCAUAAAUAAAUCAUUUGGCCAAGGAUUCUCUGAAAAGACUGUGAUGAUUUAGUGGAGAAAACAGUGGAUUAAAAAUUAGAGGACUGGCUAGGAGCAGUGGCUCACACCUGUAAUCUCAGCACUUUGACAGUCUGAGGCAAGAGCAUCCCUUGAGGCCAGGAGUUCGAGACUAGCCUGGGCAACAUAAGGAGACCAUGUCUCUAUAAAUAAUUUUUACAUUUUUGAAAAAAUUAGCUGGGCAUGGUGGUGCAUGCCGGUGGUCCCACCUACUUAGGAGGCGGAGGCAGGAGGAUGACCUUAGCGUGGGAGGUUGAGGCUGUAGUGAGCUGUGAUCACACCACCGUACUCCAACCUGGAUAACGAAGUGAGAACCUGUCUCAAAAAAAAAAGAGGACUUUGGGUUUAGUUUUAACUUUGCUAUUUUUAGCUAUAUAAAUGUUUUUAAACUGUAGUAAAAUUAUAUAACAUAAAAUUUGCCAUUUUAACAAAUUUUUUUCCAAUUUUACUGUGAUGAAAUACAGUAACAAAAUUUGUCAUUUUAACCAUUUUUAAGUAUACAGUUUGGUGAUAUUAAAUACAUUCAUAAUGUUACACAACGAUCCAUACUAUCUGCCUCUGUAACUCUUUUCAUCUUGUAAAACCAAAGCUCUAUACCCAUUAAAUAGUAACUCCUAUUUCCCCCUCUCCCCAGACCCUGGGACCUAUCAAUCUACUGUCUUUAUGUUUAUGAUUUUGAUUAAGCAUCUCAUAUAAAUAGAACCAUACAUUAUUUGCCUUUUUGUGACUGGCUUAUUUCACUUAGCAUUAUGUCCUCAAGGUUCAUCCAUGUUGUAGCAUCAGCAAUUUCUUCCUGGCCGGUCACAGUGGCUCACGCCUAUAAUCCCAGCACUUUGGGAGGCUGAGGUGGGCAGAUCACCUGAGGUCAGGAGUUCGAGACCAGCCUGACCAACAUGGUGAAACCUCAUUUCUACUAAAAAUACAAAAAUUAGCUGGAUGUGGUGGCGGGUGCCUGUGAUCCCAGCUACUUGGGACGUUGAGGCAGGAGAAUUGUUUGAACUGGGAGGCAGAGGUUGCAGUGAGCCGAUAUCACACCACUGCACUCCAGACUGGGCAACAGAGUGAGACUCUCUGAAAAAAAAAAAAAAAAAAAAAAAAAAGAAAG